CUUCCACUCCAGCAUCGGAUCCCGGAAAGGCAGCGUCGGAGACUGGACCCAAAACUCUUCCUGUUCUGCCUGCAGAGUUGAGCCCCGUCCGGGUCCUGGACCCGCGUAGUACUGACCCUGGAUCCCUGUUCACUGCGUUCUCGCUCCCCGCGCUCCCUGCUGGACCCCGGGAUGCCGGGCAUCUCCGCCCGAGGCCUCUCUCAUGAGGGGAGGAAGCAGCUAGCUGUUAACCUCACCCGUGUCCUGGCACUCUACCGUUCCAUCUUGGAUGCCUACAUCAUCGUGAGGCCACAGGGGCGUGGGUGGGAUGUCUCUGGUCGUGUGGUUGGCUAGGUGCCCACGUCAGGGAGAGAAUCUGGAGAAUUAGCCUCUGAUCUCUUUCCUUCUAUGAGUUUCAGUCUUUUUCUGUACAAGAAGGGGUUAAAACUGGAGUGAUCCCUCCUUUUUUUUCAGCUGACAUAAAUAAUAUUUCUUUUUUUUUCUUUUUCUUUUUUUUUUUCUUUUUUUUUUUGAGACGGAGUCUCGCUCUGUCCCCCAGGCUGGAGUGCAGUGGCACGAUCUCGGCUCACUGCAUAAAUAAUAUUUCUAGUACCUACCUAGAUUGUUUUUGUAAUCUUCCCAGAUCCAAGGAAUUUUUCACAGACAACCUAUGGGACACACUCCCUUGCUCAUGGCAGGAAGCAUUGGAUGGACUGAAACCACCACAGCUGGCCACAAUGCUGCUGGGGAUGCCUGGGGAAGGGGAGGUCGUCAGGUAUGGGCUAGAAGGUCCCUGUGCUGGGGAACUCAAGGCUUUAAGCCCUGCAGUGAGCAUAUUGCUCAGAGAGUCUCAUAAGGUCUUCCUGGGCCUCGGGUUGUAAACUGCUGCACUCAGAUGUGAUGGGACUAUUCACUGGAGGCCUCGGCUGGACUAUCUCAGGUACAGGUCAGUGUGGCCACUCACCCUGCUGGCCCUGAAGUCCACGGCGUGUGCCCUGGCCUUUACCCGGAUGCCUGGCUUUCAGACCCCCUCAGAAUUCCUGGAGAACCCCAGCCAGAGCUCCCGACUAACAGCUCCAUUCCGGAAACAUGUCAGGCCCAAGAAGCAGCAUGAGAUCCGGAGGCUGGGAGAGUUGGUGAAGAAGCUGAGUGAUUUCACAGGCUGCACCCAGGUUGUAGACGUGGGCUCAGGCCAGGGCCAUCUCUCCCGCUUCAUGGCUCUUGGCCUGGGGUUGAUGGUGAAGAGCAUCGAAGGGGAUCAGAGACUGGUGGAGAGAGCCCAGCGCCUGGACCAGGAGCUUCUGCAGGCUCUGGAGAAAGAGGAGAAGAGGAACCCGCAGGUGGUCCAAACCAGCCCUCGUCACUCCCCACACCACGUGGUUAGGUGGGUAGACCCCACAGCCCUGUGUGAGGAGCUUCUGCUUCCACUGGAGAACCCGUGUCAGGGCAGGGCCCGCUUGCUGCUCACAGGCCUCCACGCCUGUGGGGAUCUGAGUGUUGCCUUGCUGAGACACUUCUCCUGCUGUCCUGAGGUGGUGGCCCUGGCCUCAGUGGGCUGCUGCUACAUGAAGCUGAGUGACCCUGGCGGCUACCCACUGAGUCAGUGGGUGGCUGGGCUGCCUGGCUAUGAACUGCCCUACCGGCUUCGGGAGGGGGCCUGCCAUGCCCUGGAGGAAUAUGCUGAGCGGCUACAGAAAGCUGGCCCUGGCCUUCGAACUCACUGCUACCGUGCAGCACUGGAGACAGUCAUCCGACGGGCCCGGCCCGAGCUCCGUCGGCCAGGCGUGCAGGGUAUCCCCAGGGUCCACGAGCUCAAGAUUGAAGAAUAUGUGCAGCGGGGGCUACAGCGAGUGGGGCUAGAUCCCCAGCUGCCACUGAAUCUGGCUGCCCUUCAGGCCCACGUGGCCCAGGAGAACCGUGUGGUGGCCUUCUUCAGCCUGGCUCUACUGCUUGCCCCACUGGUGGAGACGCUUAUUCUACUGGACCGGCUGCUGUACCUUCAGGAACAGGCCCUUUCUCCCAGGUUUCCAUGCUGAGCUCCUGCCCAUCUUCAGUCCUGAACUCUCUCCCAGAAACCUGGUUCUGGUGGCCACCAAGAUGCCCCUGGGUCAGGCUCUUUCUGUUCUGGAGACUGAAGACAGCUGAUGCAGCCUGAGGAAACAUCUCAGACCCCAUCAUCUGAAAGUGCCCAGAGAGCACAGUGGCAGAGUACAUCUCAUCCAGAGAAACAGCAUCCUGCAUCCUCCAGAGUCCUGGUUCCUUCAGUUUCAUCCCCUUUCUCUCCUUCCAUGGAUUAUGUAAUACAUUGUAAAGUUUUAAUUAAUUAAAAAUUGGAUAUCUGUUUCCUUCCCA